GUCUGUCCCGGCCGCAGCCCCACGCCGGCUGCAGCUCCGCGAGCCGAGCCGGAUCUCGAGCGGGGUACACGGGCUGAGGCGGCGGCGGCGGCCCCGCCCCGGGGCUCCAUUGUUAAGGCGGCUGCGGCUCUGUCGGCUGUUCAGCUGCGCUCCAGUCGGCCCAGGCGCCGCGGCGAGGAGCGAGCGCUGCGAGGUGGCGGCCUGAGAACACACACUUCCAUGUAGAAGUGGUAAAGUGUGAAUGUGGUCUUUUUGCUUUUUUGAAGCAAAGAUCACUGAGCUGCUAAUUCCUAAAACCGCUGAUAUUUUUGGAUGGCAGCUAUUGUUCACUGAGCAGAGCUCGCUCUGUCAUUCAUUAGGUUUCUGUCCUUGAGUCCUGAGAGUUAGUUUUCUCACCUGUAAAAUGAUAGUAUCUACUCUGGAGACAUUAUUUUAAAAAACUCGAGUGACUUGUUUGGAAAGUUGAUUGGCAUUGCAUGAAACAUGUAAGGGAGGCCAGAUUUGGUUUCUUUGGGGUGGGGAAUAGCUACAGAUUUUGAGCACUUACUAUGUGUUAUGCUGGGGAGUAGACAAAGUUACAGAUUAUCUUUGGUUAAUCCUCAUAACCGCUCUUUAAAGUGGAGAUUAUCCUUUAAGAGCUUUUUUUAAAAAAAUCUUUAACAGAUAAUAAUUAUACUGAUAAUGACCGUAGUAAUUUAUUGGAGACUUCUUACGAGCUAAGGACUGUGCUAAAUUUAAAUUCUUCACAUAAUGACAUUUAAAGAACUGACCGACAAGCCUCUGAUGAUCCUCGUUUUUAGAGGUGAGGUAGCACAGCACUGUACUCAAGGCCAUGCCUGGCAAGUGCUGGAGCAGAGUUCCAGCCUCAACCCUCCACCACCGAAGUCUGUGUUCAUUCGCUGUGUCCAGAUCGUUCUAUCAUCACAUCCUCCUGGAGUCUGGAUUUCAUCCAUUCCCUGUGGCAGCCCCAGCCCUGCGAAGCGGCAAUGGAAGAGUUAAUAGUUGAACUUCGUCUCUUUCUUGAACUCCUGGACCAUGAAUAUCUAACCUCAACUGUCAGGGAGAAAAAGGCAGUGAUAACCAACAUUCUGCUAAGAAUACAGUCAUCCAAAGGUUUUGAUGUGAAGGACCAUGCUCAGAAGCAGGAGACCGCUAACAGCCUGCCAGCCCCUCCUCAGAUGCCCCUGCCGGAGAUCCCUCAGCCCUGGCUGCCUCCUGACAGUGGGCCUCCACCAUUGCCAACAUCCUCCCUCCCAGAAGGUUAUUAUGAGGAAGCUGUGCCGCUGAGCCCCGGAAAAGCUCCGGAAUACAUCACAUCAAAUUAUGAUUCCGAUGCGAUGAGCAGCUCUUAUGAGUCGUAUGAUGAAGAGGAGGAGGAUGGGAAGGGGAAGAAAACCCGGCACCAGUGGCCCUCCGAGGAGGCCUCCAUGGACCUGGUCAAGGACGCCAAAAUCUGCGCCUUCCUGCUGCGGAAGAAGCGGUUCGGCCAGUGGACCAAGUUGCUCUGCGUCAUCAAAGACACCAAACUGCUGUGCUAUAAAAGUUCCAAGGACCAGCAGCCUCAGAUGGAACUGCCACUCCAAGGCUGUAACAUUACGUACAUCCCGAAAGACAGCAAAAAGAAGAAGCACGAGCUGAAGAUUACUCAGCAGGGCACGGACCCGCUUGUUCUCGCCGUCCAGAGCAAGGAACAGGCCGAGCAGUGGCUGAAGGUGAUCAAAGAAGCCUACAGUGGUUGUAGUGGCCCCGUGGAUUCAGAGUGUCCUCCUCCACCAAGCUCCCCGGUGCACAAGGCAGAACUGGAGAAGAAACUGUCUUCAGAGAGACCCAGCUCAGAUGGGGAGGGUGUUGUGGAAAAUGGAAUUACCACAUGUAAUGGAAAGGAGCAAGUGAAGAGGAAGAAAAGUUCCAAAUCAGAGGCCAAGGGCACUGUGUCGAAAGUCACUGGGAAAAAAAUCACCAAGAUCAUCAGUCUGGGAAAGAAAAAGCCGUCCACAGACGAGCAGACCUCCUCAGCUGAGGAAGAUGUUCCCACCUGCGGCUAUCUGAACGUGCUCUCCAACAGCCGCUGGCGAGAGCGCUGGUGCCGAGUGAAAGAUAACAAGCUCAUUUUCCACAAGGACAGGACCGACCUGAAGACCCAUAUUGUGUCUAUUCCGCUCCGUGGCUGCGAGGUGAUCCCGGGUUUGGAUUCUAAACAUCCUCUGACGUUCCGGCUGCUGCGCAACGGCCAGGAGGUUGCAGUAUUGGAGGCAUCUUCUUCUGAAGACAUGGGCAGGUGGAUUGGGAUUUUACUCGCAGAGACGGGAUCGUCCACAGACCCGGAGGCUCUGCACUAUGACUACAUUGAUGUGGAGAUGUCUGCAAGUGUCAUUCAGACAGCCAAACAGACCUUCUGUUUCAUGAACAGGCGUGUUAUAUCUGCUAACCCAUAUCUAGGGGGCACCUCCAACGGCUAUGCCCACCCCAGCGGGACGGCACUUCAUUAUGACGAUGUCCCGUGCAUCAACGGCUCGCUCAAGGGUAAAAAGCCCCCCGUGGCGUCUAAUGGGGUCACAGGAAAAGGGAAGACUCUGAGCAGUCAGCCAAAGAAAGCGGAUCCCGCGGCUGUUGUGAAAAGGACGGGUUCGAAUGCUGCCCAGUACAAGUAUGGCAAGAACCGGGUAGAAGCAGAUGCCAAGCGGCUACAGACCAAAGAGGAGGAGCUGCUGAAGAGGAAAGAGGCCCUGCGGAAUAGGCUGGCCCAGCUCCGCAAGGAAAGAAAAGACCUUCGAGCGGCUAUUGAAGUGAACGCCGGCAGGAAGCCGCAGGCGAUCCUGGAGGAGAAGCUGAAGCAGCUGGAGGAGGAGUGCCGGCAGAAGGAGGCGGAGCGUGUCAGCCUGGAGCUGGAGCUGACGGAGGUCAAGGAGAGCCUGAAGAAAGCGCUGGCGGGCGGAGUCACCCUGGGGCUGGCCAUCGAGCCCAAGUCAGGGACAUCGAGUCCACAGUCUCCAGUGUUCCGGCACCGGACCCUGGAAAACUCGCCCAUCUCCAGCUGUGACACCAGUGACACCGAGGGCCCCGUGCCGGUGAACAGCGCGGCCGUCUUGAAGAAGAGCCAGGCUGCCCCGGGCAGCUCCCCCUGCCGAGGGCAUGUGCUGCGGAAGGCCAAGGAAUGGGAAUUGAAGAACGGGACCUAGGGGACAGCAGCACCACUCCAGCCUCAGAGACUGCACACCCCCUUGCCUGUAUCCUCAUCUGUGUGACGGCAGGAAGCUCUGCCCAGAGUGGCCUCAGCUGCACGACUCCAGAGGCUCCACGACUGAGCUCUGAGGCCAGUGCCUGUCCCCCAGGCCCACUUGUAUUCUUUCUACUGUAAAAUGGCGCCUUUAAAAAAGAUGUAAGACUUUGGUUCCCAACUUUGUUAAAAAACAAAAAAAGUGAUGGAAAGGUGUUUGAAAGGAUGCUAUCAGGCGAAGUGACAUCUUUCUAACCAGAUAGGCCAUUGCUUUCACCGAUUCCAACCCAGCCCUGGACUGAGGAUGGAUGGUUCCAUGAGCCCCCAGAUGAAAACCUGGAUUCGACAGGGAAGAGCUUGGAUCCCCGGCUGCCCCGGGCAUGAGUGUGGCUGGCCAUGGGCACUGGGCUCGCCUUGCACGCCCACCAGGAGGGCCAGGGGCAUACGCAGUCCUGACGUGGACUUUGUGUCUUGGCGUACCCUCUCCACGUGCCCGUCCCCCUCGUCAUCAGAGGUAAAGGCAUGAGAAAAUCGCGCUGUGAAACGUUUUUUACCUUUUAUUAUUAUUUUUUGGACAGAUGCUUUUGUCACCAAGACAUGAAAAGCUGCCAUUCUUCUUAACCUGUUUUUUAGGAAUGUCUUUUUACUGUGUGUCACACUUAGAUCAAGGAGUUUUCAGAGGUUCCUUAUUUUAUUAAUUAAUUAUUUGUGCUGCUUUUGACAGGUAGCAGAGGGUUUUAAUACUUCACUAACAGUACACCCUCCUCCCCCUUGGGCUAGCAUCCCCAGCCCUUAAUCCACGUCGGAGCCGGCAGGUGCUUCUCACACCAGGAGCCUCUGGGGGCAGGGGCUGGCUCCUCGCCGCUGUACAGGACGUUUACUGCUGCUUGGGGCCAGGGCAGUCCUUUGAAAGGGAAGCAAGUUCCGGAAUUUGUUCGCUCAUGGAACUAUAACACCUUAGAGCAAGAGGCAGGAAUUCCAGGGCCUCCUGCCCCUCCCCUUCCUCCAGCUUGUCAAGUUAAACCACUAAUGUGUUGGUGGGCCUGGCCGUGCUGCCUCUCCUGAGUAGGGUGGGUGCAAGUAGGGCCUCUUUCCCAGCUUUCUUGCUUGCCUUCUGUGCAAUAUUUCUUGGAGAAUUUGGAUGCCUAAGGCAUAAAGGAAAAAAACAGAGUUCAUAGUUUGAGCUGGUAUUUACCCCCUGGGUUUAAAAAUCAGAUUAACUUCUUGGUCUCCCGGAGGCUGCUGUCAGGAAUUCUCCAGUACGGGAAGAUGCAGUCACUUAUGACGAAAUAAGUCACCCCUGAACGCCUCCGCAGGCAGAUUCAUGGAGACCAGUCCCAGUAGCAACCGCCCCUUCCCCAAGCAUAGAAUACAGAGGUGCCAUACUUGGUGUAAGCCUUCCUUCUGUCCACUGUCCAGAAUGUCCUUUUUCACACAGAGGAAGAGAUGGCGGGAAAACACUGACUGACUCCUUGGGUUUCCCCCAGACAUACUUUCAGAGCGCUAGCUGUGUGGUGCACGGGACUUUACAGUUAGGAUUCAUGUUUAAGGUGGUGGCGCUUGAGGCCUGCAAGGGCCACGUUGGAUUACUGAAGCGGAAAGCGGUCUCCCAUGUAUAAGAAAAAGUUUUACAACACGAAUUGGAAGCUGCUUGAGUCCACCUGAACUUGAAUUGAUUGCAAAGCCAUCUGCUGGGAACGGUUUUGGGUUCCUGAGCCAUCAGCCAGCCUUUCUUUCCCCUCUGAUGCACGUUCCUCCCGGCCUAGUCCGUGGAGGCCCAUCACACCAGCAUCCGUGACGCCAGCUUCCCACUAGGACAUCCAGGCAGGUCGGGCGGGGACGCCACACACCUCAGGGCCGUCCGCUGCAUUGCCAUAGAGGAGCCCUCCCUCCAGUGGUCACUUCCCACCAUUGCAGGCAGACUUCCCACCAUUGCAGGCAGCUGGGCCCACUUCAUAUCACACAAAAUGAAUUUUCUAUAAAGGGAAAAAAGUUUGCUCCUCCAUAGAUUUUUGCUGCCUUCGGGUCAAAUAGUUUCCCUGGUUGACACUCUUGGGCCACUCUGAUUGGCAGCCUGCUUUGCCAAAGAGAACUGUGUGAGGUUUUGGUGGUUAGUAAGAGAAGGGGGAGAUGGCCAGCCUGAAGUCACGGUCCUGGCCCAGCACAGGUGGGCAGCAGCGAGCUGGCAGGUGAAGUGUGAGCAGCACGCAAAGUGUCACGUGGGCCUUAGCCGUCACCCACCAGCUUCCUCACCAGGCAAGGAGGCCCCGGAGCCUUAGCAGGGACUUGCCCAACGGCACAGCUGAUUGGUGCUCGACUCCCAGCAUGCAUAUUUUGUUGUAAAAACCCAGGUUUGUAAUUCACAUCCACAACCCUAAGCCUUUUAAAGCGGAGGCAAACGUUAACAAACCCCAUCGUGGUCCAUGGAGCCUUUCAAAAUGGGUGCCCUGGAGGGGCCUGACAGUGGGUUCCUUCCAUGGCGGAUACUCCCUUGAAAUUUCACAUUCCAUCAAAGUUUAAAGCAUUUACUUCAGAAUAAGUUAUUUAUGUGUAUAUGUUCAAUAAAUAUAGUUUUUAAUUUAUAUCUGUACAUAUUAGACACACGCGAGCCAUCUUGCCAGAAUUCUGACAGUGAUGUCAUUUUAUUCCCCUCCCAAAACAUGCCCCAGGAACAAGCACCCCUUGCCUCUGUGGCAGCUGCGAGUGUGUCUGAUUUCAUAACGAAGCCAGGCUGAGGGCAAGAGGCCCGACAGGCAGGCCAGGGUCCCCGGAGAAGCCGGAUUUCUUCGCAAUGUCACUGGUACUUAGCAGAUGGUCGUGUUCACAGGGGCUAGCCACCUGUACUACGGUGCCGACCGCAAUGCGAGGAAUGUGGUGGCCACGCGAUGGAGCUGGCCGGAGGACAGGUCAGGUGAGGGGGCCGACCCCUGCGGGGCUCAGGGCUCCUUCCAUUCUAACCUUGAGCCACAGUGUCACUCUUCAGGGCUCUGCUCCUGGCUCUAUUUUGUUAAGGUGUCAUCAGCCUUCAACCUCCAUUUAUAUAUUUUUAUAAUGUUAAGCCACUGACCAACUUUUUCAUAGAAACAACUAUCAGAUUCGAGGGCUCCCUUUGUCCCCCUGACCUGGGCACAGGCAUGGGCGAUGGCUCCCUCUUCCCAGAAUCUGCGGGGAACUGGGGCAAGGCCCAUCUGUCUGCAAGGCUGGUAGCUCUCUCCCUCGGCUUCCAGAGUCCACGGCAGUUGCAAGGUAACCAGUGUGGAUCUGCUGAGUCACCCCAGGCACCAGACUUACCCCAGGAGCAUGGGCCACUGUCCAUGGGGCCUUCCUUGAGACCUUCCCUUGGGGCUGGCGGGCGGCGGCUUACCAGCUGGGUCAGUCCCAUCUCGCCCCUCUGUGCCUAUGCCCUGGCGUUGCCAGGCUUAACCUUCCCCUGUAUCUUACUCAUCCCAGAAUUAUUACUGGCCAUUUCUAAAUAGACAAAAACUACCCUAAAAUGUGGAGAUUUACUCCUUUUGAAAAGUCUGUUUCAAAAAGUGUGGCCUCAGCUCUGGAGGCCACCCCCAGGAAGGAGUUUGAGGUUCAUUGUCAUUAUGGCCACAGUUUGGUGCUUGUGCACGGGACUCAAAGGGCAGCGUCGAAGCUGGGGUUAGGUGUAGGGUUGUGAGCAAAGCUCCCCUGUUUGUGGCCACACCUUCCCUUUCCAAAAAGGCUAUUAAUUCUACUCACCCACUAUUUGGGGGGAUGUAAAUUUUGCCCACAGACUUUGCCACCCAGGUGAGGUGCUGUGUUCAUGCACGGAACUGAUGUCAUUAGACACCAUCCAAGGAUGGGCAGCCUGCAGUGUGGCCGGCGACUGCCAUCCAGAGAAAAGGCACCUUGUGCCACAGGGCGGGGCCGACACCCUGAGCUCACAGGUGGCCCCUGCAUUCAGGUGGAUGUCCAUCCUUGAAACAGCCUCUUCUGGGAACACAGCACUGGAGGUCUCCAGGCAUCAGGGUUGGCCGGCAGGGUGCCCUGCAGCUUACAUAAAGGUCGUGGCAAUGUUUCAAUGUUAAACUAAACUAUUGCCUUCCUCUUACUUUUCCUAAAAUGAUUUUCUAAUGGGAACAGUCACUUCAAGUUCAUGACAUAGUUUGAAGGAGGAUAAUUCAUUUUUUCCUGGUUGUCACUGUCUUCUUAUCCCCUUGGUGGGCUGGGUUCAUACUGUGAAAUAAACUAAAAUGAAACCAAAACGUUCCUGCCGUAAAUACGUGGCACAGCACUGCAGAAAAAGCAGUCACCUCUAUUCGUGAGUCCCCAAGCCAUAGCAGGGCGUCUGUAAAAGAAGGGAAACUGCACCCAGGAAGUGGUGGGCGUCAGACGCAUCCUUUCGCCCGUAGUUCAUGAAAUAGUUCCGGCUUUGGUCUUCCAGAAAAUCUCAACUUCACCGUGCACAAGUGUUACCGGGUCUUUUUAGUGUAGCCAUGGAAGAUACUUUCAAAAGGACAUCUUCAGAUCAUAAGUCUUAGGACCAAAGGUGUUUUUAAUGAGAUAAUCUUUUUGAUUUUCUAACAAGAAAGGAAAUAUUCACUUUACAUUUUAACAUCAACUUUUAAGUGAUAUUCAGAAUUAAUUGACCAUGGUGAUACGUUGUAAAAUGUUUUCAUAUUAAGAAUGUAAUUAUUUCCUUAUUGUAUUUUUUAAAAGCUAAAGUCAUAUUUAAAAUUCUCUUUGAAAGAAACAGGCAAAGAAACAGCAAAGAUUUUUUUAAAUUAAAUAUGUUAGUAGUGCCCACUUCAAAUGACUGUAAAUAUAUUUUCACUGUUUCUCAAUGUAUUUAAUUCAUAAAGUAAAAAUUUUAUGAAAAGAAACUUGCAAGGAAAAUCCUAGUUUUCAGUCCACUCGCCCCACUUUGUAGUAGCUUCACUGAAUUUCCUGCUUUCCUGGUUGAAUUUUCUACUGUUUCACGUGGUGUAACCCUAGACUGGCGCCCUUGGCGUGCCCCUUUGUGUAUGAAUAAACUUCUCUCCCCCAG